ACUCGCGCGCCCCAUCCCUCCCAGGCUGCCAGCGCAGCUAGGUGCAGAGGGAUCCCAGGAGCCGCGCGCGCCCCGCAGUUUCCGCGCUAAGGGAACGAGUGCGCGGAGGGGACGAGCGGCUGGACCACAGCCGGCGCCCGAUCAGGAUCUCCGCGCUGGGAUCGGUGGAACUUGAGGCAGCGGCGGCGCGGGGCGCCAUGGCACACCGAGCGGCUCCGUCUUCUGCUCCUCAGAGAGCCCGGCUGGCGGCCUGGGAUGACAAGGUACCAUCCCUCCAGAGGCUGAUCCCAAUGCAUCGGCUUCGCUUAUCUAGACCCAGAUUUAAUCAACUCACCCCCUGAGACACCCAGCCACAGCUUCUGCUGGCUGAGCCUGACACUGAGUUUGGACCAGAUUCCCCAAGCUAGGGAGACGCAUAGAGAAAGAAGGGUACUCGAGCUAACCCAUCCCCAUUCUGAGCUGCUCUGCGGGGGAUUGGGUAGAAAGGGUCUCAGAAGAGGGAAAUCGGCACAGAUUCCGCUUCUCGCCGUUGCGGGGUUCCCUGCGGGCGGCACUGCGAGUUCCUCACCCGGGCACGUCCUCACUCCCCGUGCCCGGGAUGAGGGAGAAAACAGCCCUUUGGCGUUUGAGCAAUUGCAGAAAGUUUCAGCGAGUUCGUUAGUUUGGAGGGAAUGUUGCGAGGCCAGGCCGAAGGGCGGGGGGGAUAGUAACGGGCGAAAGUCGAACUGUGAGUAAGACCUGGAGAAGGCGACCGUCCUGGGGGUAGCCUAGGCAGUUCCACUCGGGCUGGGCGCAGGAAAGGCUGGCUCCGGAAUUCCCAGCCUCCGGGAAAGCUAGCUGCUCGGGAAACGCCAAUCGAAUUAGCUCAGAGAAGAGUGGCCGUGGCCUUGUGUAUCCAGUGUCUGUGCCUCAGGCUUCAACCCCCUAGGGAAAGAGUGACAAGCAAAUACUUCGCCUUGAAUGUUGCUACUCUGAAGCUGUAACUGGACAGGAUCUUGGCCGAGGUGCACAGUGAGCGUGGCCCGCCCCCUUCCUCAUCGCGAAUCAGAAUUUCUACACAGGGGCAGCUAGACCAGAAAACCUUCCCAGAGACUCACCACUCUGCUUUUCAUGGGUUCAACAUGUCUGGACUGCAAUCCUGCACAGUUUUGAGAGGGAGAUGACUUGAGUGGUUGGCUUUUAUCUCCACAACAAUGUCCAUGAACAAUUCCAAACAGCUAGUGUCUCCUGCAGCUGCGCUUCUUUCAAACACAACCUGCCAGACGGAAAACCGGCUUUCCGUAUUUUUUUCAGUAAUCUUCAUGACAGUGGGAAUCUUGUCAAACAGCCUUGCCAUCGCCAUUCUCAUGAAGGCAUAUCAGAGAUUUAGACAGAAGUCCAAGGCAUCGUUUCUGCUUUUGGCCAGUGGCCUGGUAAUCACUGAUUUCUUUGGCCAUCUCAUCAAUGGAGCCAUAGCAGUAUUUGUAUAUGCUUCUGAUAAAGAAUGGAUCCGCUUUGACCAAUCAAAUGUCCUUUGCAGUAUUUUUGGUAUCUGCAUGGUGUUUUCUGGUCUGUGCCCACUUCUUCUAGGCAGUGUGAUGGCCAUUGAGCGGUGUAUUGGAGUCACAAAACCAAUAUUUCAUUCUACGAAAAUUACAUCCAAACAUGUGAAAAUGAUGUUAAGUGGUGUGUGCUUGUUUGCUGUUUUCAUAGCUUUGCUGCCCAUCCUUGGACAUCGAGACUAUAAAAUUCAGGCGUCGAGGACCUGGUGUUUCUACAACACAGAAGACAUCAAAGACUGGGAAGAUAGAUUUUAUCUUCUACUUUUUUCUUUUCUGGGGCUCUUAGCCCUUGGUGUUUCAUUGUUGUGCAAUGCAAUCACAGGAAUUACACUUUUAAGAGUUAAAUUUAAAAGUCAGCAGCACAGACAAGGCAGAUCUCAUCAUUUGGAAAUGGUAAUCCAGCUCCUGGCGAUAAUGUGUGUCUCCUGUAUUUGUUGGAGCCCAUUUCUGGUUACAAUGGCCAACAUUGGAAUAAAUGGAAAUCAUUCUCUGGAAACCUGUGAAACAACACUUUUUGCUCUCCGAAUGGCAACAUGGAAUCAAAUCUUAGAUCCUUGGGUAUAUAUUCUUCUACGAAAGGCUGUCCUUAAGAAUCUCUAUAAGCUUGCCAGUCAAUGCUGUGGAGUGCAUGUCAUCAGCUUACAUAUUUGGGAGCUUAGUUCCAUUAAAAAUUCCUUAAAGGUUGCUGCUAUUUCUGAGUCACCAGUUGCAGAGAAAUCAGCAAGCACCUAGCUUAAUAGGACAGUAAAUCUGUGUGGGGCUAGAACAAAAUUAAGACAUGUUUGGCAAUAUUUCAGUUAGUUAAAUACCUGUAGCCUAACUGGAAAAUUCAGGCUUCAUCAUGUAGUUUGAAGAUACUAUUGUCAGAUUCAGGUUUUGAAAUUUGUCAAAUAAACAGGAUAACUGUACAUUUUUCACUUGUUUUUGCCAAUGGGAGGUAGACACAAUAAAAUAAUGCCAUGGGAGUCACACUGAAAGCAAUUUUGAGCUUAUCUGUCUUAUUUAUGCUUUGAGUGAAUCAUCUGUUGAGGUCUAAUGCCUUUACUUGGCCUAUUUGCCAGAGAACAUCUUAAUGCAGCCUGCAUAGUGAAAUGGUUAUUUUGAGAUCACCGCUCUGUAGCUAACCCUUAUAAACUAGGCUCAGUAAAAUAAAGCACUCUUAUUUUUUGAUCUGGCCUAUUUUGCCCCUCAUUGUGUAGCCUCAAUUAACACAUGCAUGGUCAUGACACCCAGAAUUCAUGAUGGUUUGUUAUAACAACCUCUGCAUAUUCCAGGUCUGGCAGACAGGUUGCCUGACCCUGCAAUCCUAUCUAGAAUGGGCCCAUUCUUGUCAUAUUUGACAAAUAGGACUGCCUACAUUUAUUAUUAUGAAGGUCGAUUGUUGUUGGAAGUGUUUUUUCAUGUCAUAGAUUAGCAAUUUUCAAAUAAUUAUUUUUUCUCUGAAAAUUUUGUGUGUGAUUGCACAAUAAAUAAUUUUUAGAGAAACAAAGGCUCUUUCUCAGCACAUUGAUGGGCAACUAGAAUUACAGCAGUUUCAAAACUCUACCAUGGAUAAUGCAAACAAACCGAAGCUACAUGCCAAUGAUAGGUGCAAAGAAUAUUGGCAAAAGGUGCUUUACCUUGAGCCAUUAUUUGUGUCAGAGAACAAAAGAAACAGAAUCAAUAUAUAAAAUUCAAAGACUAUCUGCAGCUAGUGUGUUUCUUCUUUACACACAUAUACACACAGACAUCAGAAAAUUCUGUUGAGAGCAGGUUCAUUAAAUUUGUAAGAUGGCAUAUUCUAAAGCCUGUGCUACCAGUACUAAGAGGGGAAGACUGGCAAUUUGCCAAGCACUUGGGGAUUAUUAUAACAAUUAACUAGGAGAUCAAGAGAUAAUAAUCUCUCCCCAAAUUUUCCAAUAAUAAUUGAGACUUUUUCUUUGCUUGUUUGUGUAAUUCAACCAAAAGAAUUUCAAUACCCAUUCAAAUUGUCCUAGGUCUAUCAGAAAUUAGGGAAGGUAGUCCUGCUUUAUAAUAGGAAAAUGUAUUUCUGUAUAAGAGUUCUUUGCUUUCAUUAACUUGGAUUCAUUUAAAAAUUAAUCUUCCCUGUUAGGCUGAUUUCAGAUUCUCUAGGAAAUCUGUGUAAGUAACCAGAAGACCUUUCAGAUGGUUUAUUUGCUUUCAGCAGAGAAUUUAUUUCAUACAGUUACUUAAGAGUGUUGAUGUCUUGUGAACAGAGAUAUAAGGAACCAUUCUCCAUCCUUCCUUAUCAUGCUGGGUACAAUGCUUCUAUGAAUAUUUCCAUGUAUUUUGACUGGGGAGAGGCAUGGAGAAGAAACUCUCAUUCAGGGGCUCCAGGAUCCUUCUCCUUGAGGCUUCUAAAUAAAUGGCAGAAUUCUUGCUGUAUUGCCAUGAUGUCACCCUGGCCAUGUGUACUGACUUGAGGAGAUCUUGCAACAUGGCCAUGUGCAAGGCUUUAAGGAGUGAGAGAGAUGUGUACAUAUCUUAGGAGGGUUAUCUAUGUUAUCUGAGUAUAUGUUUGGGUAACCAAAUUGGUCUUAAAAAUGAUGUUAACCCAAGAAGUAGACAUCAAAAAUUAAAAAAAAAAAAAGGAAUGUGUUUUCAUUGUUUUAAGUUUUUCUUCUGAGUAAAACAAAAUUAUAGAAAACAAAUGCAACAAUGUGCACAUCUGACUUAAGAGUUUCAUUUCUGUUAUUAUAUGUGUUGCAUGUAGCUUGGCGAUUUACUGUGUAAUGAAUAAUAGACUGGAACAUCUACCAAUAACUUUCACAUAAAUGUUCAAAAUAGAAGUGUAUUUUUUCAGGUUUCUGGAAAUAAAUAGUAAAAUAAAUGGCACAAAUAGUUUCAAUAAAUUUACCAAUUUGAGUGUUUUCAGCUCUAUUUCAAAACUCAUAACUAAUCUUCAGAAUUACUGAAUUUCCUUUUGAACUGGGUAAGGCAUUAUCCAAGCAACUUCACAUACUAUUUAAACAUGAUUUCUCGGUAAUUAUAUAUUCUGGGCAAAUAACAUAAACAUGUCAGGAUUUUUACAGGUGUUAGUGAAUUUUUCUAAAAAGAUGAGACAAAAGCAAAAAUAUCACACAUAGGUUUUUAUGACUAUGAAUACAAAGAUAAUGCUGAUUCACAAUUAGCUAUGGGUAAGUCCAAAACAUCAGACCUUUUACUGAUGGGUUAACUAGGUGAAAGAAAUGGGCCCUUAUUUUUUUUUUUCCCUAGAGGCAGAAAGUUACUUCUAAUGAUCUAUAUAGCUAAAACGAAAAAUACCUGAAAGUUAAUACAUACAUAUGUAGAUAUAUUUUGUUAUGUGAUAAAUGUUUCUUGUUUGCACACUUUUGGACUUGAGAAAUCUGCUUUUGUUUUGUGCCUACUCUGAGUUUAGAACCCAAAUAAGAGGACUUGUUAAAUAUAGAGUGUACUUUUUGUUAAAACUAUUGCUAGCUUCACCUGUAUACCAUCAUUGUUCCAAAUUAAAUAACUGUUUUGGGUCAGAAUAUAAAUGCUGGGAAUAUACAUUUUAUUACUUCUUAAUCUGGGUGUCAAAGAUUUUACCACCUGGUAAAUAAUGUUGGACUUCAACUUGUUACUGGCACAUUUUAAUAGUAGAUGAAACAUGUUUUUCUUGGUUAUGUGAAUAAAUGUAUGUUGUGCUCUUCAUACUUGUUGGAUUGUAUAGAGAUUAAAUAGUGAUAUGUAUAUUUUGUUGUUUGCUUUGGUAUGCAACUCAUGUAAUUUUAGUGCUUUGACUAGCUUAAAACUUCAAACAAGUAAUUUUAUAAUAAAGUUGGACUAAUGUUUUUCAAGAGUGAUUAUUUUUAGAAGGACCAUAUAAAACUUGAAACGCUUGAACCUAAACUCCCGUUUUAUCUGCUACUGGAUGAGAAGAAUUUCAACUUAAUUUCCAUUAUUACCUUUUGCUCUCCCACCCUGCCCAAUCUUCUGUGAUAUCUUCUCUCUUUUACCUGUGUCUCAACUUACCUAGGCAAGUCAUAAUUUAGAUAGAAAUCUGAUUUCCCAAACCUCCAGGUUUAGAUAUAUCAUUCAGAAAAGCCUCAAUGUGUCUGUAAUAAGAAACAAUCUCCAAAUUACAGCGCCAUAAACUUCACAAAAGUUUGUAUCUCCCACAUGGUUCCUGUCCACUCUGAAGGGGAGCUCUGCUGUUGUAAUCACUCAGAGAACUCAGGUGAAAAAACAGCCACCAUUAUAUGUGGCUGUUUCUCAAACUACAGAGCAUGGUGAAUCACACACAGGCUGUUAGAAUAUCCAUCUGGAGGCAACACACAUUUGCAUACACUUCUCCAGCUAACAUAAAUAAUGUGGCUUUACUAACUUCCCAGGGGGCAGCUAAGUGCAAUACUAUAUGUUAGGAAAACGGAAACUAAUUUGUAGACAGCACUAAUGAUUUCCACAUUAGGUAAAAAAAAUUUUCAUUCUUGUCUUCCUAAUAGCAUUUAAACAGAAACGAUUUUUAAAAGUUGUUUUAAACAUUUAGAAACAUCAUGGCAUAGAAACAUUUAGGACUCACUCUUUGUAAGUACUGACAAGCAUGGUCUUGUAAUCUGUAAAGAUAAGGUAGAAUAAAUGAACUAAAAGAAAUUUUAGAUGACUAAAAGGACUAUAUAAUAGAAAGAGGGAAAUCUUGGUUCUUAAAAAUUCAGGCAAUUGAAACAUUUCUGUAUAAUACCAAGCAUUGUUGCAGUAUUGUCUGAAAUGGUUGCUUUUCUAAUAAAUGAAAAUGACUAAAAUGUA